AGAUGUGGGCGGCCUGUGUGAACCUGUCGUGCAAAGCUCACGUCACCAACUGCUGCAGUUAUCUCCUGAAUCAGGCUGAGGGUCUUUGCUGUGCACCCAGAGAUAGUUGGGUGACAAAUCACCUCCAGGUUGGGGAUGCCUCAGACUUGUGAUGGGACUGGGCAGAUGCAUCUGGGAAGUAACUGCUGCAAGAACGGACAGACACUGCUGCAGAGAACUUGCCACGGUGUUUCAUGCUGUGGCUGGUGGUUCCAGGCUGCACGCUCCAUUCUAGGAAAGGGCUGGACCUUGGAGAGUGAGGCCCUGAGGCGAGACAUGGGCACCUGGCUCCUGGCCUGCAUCUGCAUCUGCACCUGUGUCUGCUUGGGAGUCUCUGUCACAGGGGAAGGACAAGGGCCAAGGUCUAGAACCUUCACCUGCCUCACCAACAACAUUCUCAGGAUCGAUUGCCACUGGUCUGCCCCAGAGCUGGGACAGGGCUCCAGCCCCUGGCUCCUCUUCACCAGCAACCAGGCUCCUGGCGGCACACAUAAGUGCAUCUUGCGGGGCAGUGAGUGCACCGUCGUGCUGCCACCUGAGGCAGUGCUCGUGCCAUCUGACAAUUUCACCAUCACUUUCCACCACUGCAUGUCUGGGAGGGAGCAGGUCAGCCUGGUGGACCCGGAGUACCUGCCCCGGAGACACGUUAAGCUGGACCCGCCCUCUGACUUGCAGAGCAACAUCAGUUCUGGCCACUGCAUCCUGACCUGGAGCAUCAGUCCUGCCUUGGAGCCAAUGACCACACUUCUCAGCUAUGAGCUGGCCUUCAAGAAGCAGGAAGAGGCCUGGGAGCAGGCCCAGCACAGGGAUCACAUUGUCGGGGUGACCUGGCUUAUACUUGAAGCCUUUGAGCUGGACCCUGGCUUUAUCCAUGAGGCCAGGCUGCGUGUCCAGAUGGCCACACUGGAGGAUGAUGUGGUAGAGGAGGAGCGUUAUACAGGCCAGUGGAGUGAGUGGAGCCAGCCUGUGUGCUUCCAGGCUCCCCAGAGACAAGGCCCUCUGAUCCCACCCUGGGGGUGGCCAGGCAACACCCUUGUUGCUGUGUCCAUCUUUCUCCUGCUGACUGGCCCGACCUACCUCCUGUUCAAGCUGUCGCCCAGGGUGAAGAGAAUCUUCUACCAGAACGUGCCCUCUCCAGCGAUGUUCUUCCAGCCCCUCUACAGUGUACACAAUGGGAACUUCCAGCUUUCUGCACCCACCAUGUGCCUCACCUCCUCCUUCUGCGAAGGUGUCUGUCCUGUGGCCAUGGGGAAGGGUCUGUGGUGUGUGUGCUGCCCUUGGGGCUCUCACUGCCUCUGGGCUCCUGCUCUGCCUGGUCCCCUGGUCUCCCCGGAUCACAUGAUGGCACCACAGCUGAGGAGUGGGCUCUGCACUUCCCCCCCUUCCACCCAUGUUGGGCUCCUACAGCCCAGGCACCAGUGAGCAACUUGGGGGUUGCAUCAGCCCCUCCCCUCCCUGCUGGGCUGUUGGUUCAUGCCCCCUGGGUGGGAGGAGGGGGAGAGGGAGAGCUCCAGUGAGUGGUCUCUGGUUUUUCCCCUCAGACUCCUCACUUUGGGCAAAGGACAAGAGGCAGUGAGGGCCCCUCCCUGGGGUCUGGGCCAAGCUGACCACUCUUCUCCAGAAUCUUCCCUCCCUGUCCCCUUCACACUGUGGCUCCAGCUUACUAUGCAGAAAAAUCCUUUUCUCUCUCAAUGAGGAGCGUAGUUUUCAAGAUUUUUGUCCAAAAAUAUAAUUUGAACCAUGAACCGGGCAUCUGGCUCUUGGCAGAGUCUCCCUCUUUCCCCAAGGUGGUAGAUGUGACUGUCAGGAGCCUGGGCAGCUGACGACAAGGCUGAGCAGGUCAGAUUGUGACUGUCCCCUGGACUGUCAUCCUGUUGCGGGCACCAGCUGUUCCCUAGAGAACUAGGACACCUGCCACGGGUUAUUUAGACCUGCGGGUGAGGAUCUGGUGCCAUAGGUUGGUCUCCAGGGAGCACUGCAGUGAUGGAGGGUGUUGUGUGUGUGAUGCAUGGGAUGGAGGCUCCUGGUCCCACCAAGGGAACAGCUUCCUUUUGGAGGCGGGGGCCUCCUGUGGCCCCACAGAAGGAUCCAGGUCUGCUGGCCAUAGCCGAGUGCUUUGAAAGUCACCAGUCCUGACAGCGAUUCGUGUGUGUGUCUGUGUGUGUGUGUGUGUGUGUUUAUGUGUCUGUGUGUGUUCGUGUGUGUGUCUGUGUGUGUGUUUGUGUGUGUAUGUCUGUGUGUGUGUGUUUAUGUGUGUGUGUCUGUGUGUGUUUAAGUCUGUGUGUGUUUGUGUGUGUGUGUCUCUGUGUGUGUGUCUGUAUCUGUGUGUGUUUGUGUCUGUGUGUGUUUGUGUGUGUGUCUGUGUGUGUUUGUGUGUGUGUGUCUGUGUGUGUGUUUAUGUGUCUGUGUAUGUUUGUGUGUGUGUUUGUGUGUGUGUGUUUGUGUUUAUGUGUGUAUGUCUGUGUGUGUCUGUGUGUCUGUGUGUGUAUGUGUCUGUGUGUGUUUAUGUGUCUGUGUGUGUUCGUGUGGUGUGUGUGUCUGUGUGUGUGUGUUUGUGUGUGUAUGUCUGUGUGUGUGUGUGUUUAUGUGUGUGUGUCUGUGUGUGUUUAUGUCUGUGUGUGUUUGUGUGUGUGUGUCUCGUGUGUGUGUGUCUGUGUGUAUCUGUGUGUGUUUGUGUGUGUGUGUGUCUCUGUGUGUGUGUGUGUUUGUGUAUGUUUGUGUGUGUGUGUGUGUGUGUUGGGAAUGCCCAGUCUCUGCAGCUGCUGAAAGGCCCUGAGGCACAUGCUGUCAGGAGCUGGCUCUGUCCUGGGCAGAUAUCACCAUCUGUACCUCGGUUCAGGCUGCCGUGGGCACCAGGCCCUGUGCUGGGGGAGUGCUGAGGAGCCUGAAGGGACUCAGGGUCCCGUGAUGAGGCUGGGCUGGCACAUGGAGGAAAGACAGAAUGUCCAAGACACAGGCGCUGCUUGGCCUCUGGGUGUGGACCUCAGGAGGGCUUCCUGGAGGAGGAGGGAUGCUGGGCUUGCCAGAAAGGAGGCAGCUGCUCCCAGGAUGAGUUCUGAACAUGCUACCUGAGCCCUUCCCUCCUCCCGUGCUCUGUUCCAGACUUGGAUGGGGGCCCACGGGGCCGGUGUGCUGUUGAGCCAGGACUGUGCUGGCACCCCACAGGGAGCCUUGGAGCCCUGCGUCCAGGAGGCCACUGCACUGCUCACUUGUGGCCCAGCGCGUCCUUGGAAAUCUGUGGCCCUGGAGGAGGAACAGGAGGGCCCUGGGACCAGGCUCCCGGGGAACCUGAGCUCAGAGGAUGUGCUGCCAGCAGGGUGUACGGAGUGGAGGGUACAGACGCUUGCCUAUCUGCCACAGGAGGACUGGGCCCCCACGUCCCUGACUAGGCCGGCUCCCCCAGACUCAGAGGGCAGCAGGAGCAGCAGCAGCAGCAGCAGCAGCAACAACAACAACUACUGUGCCUUGGGCUGCUAUGGGGGAUGGCACCUCUCAGCCCUCCCAGGAAACACACAGAGCUCUGGGCCCAUCCCAGCCCUGGCCUGUGGCCUUUCUUGUGACCAUCAGGGCCUGGAGACCCAGCAAGGAGUUGCCUGGGUGCUGGCUGGUCACUGCCAGAGGCCUGGGCUGCAUGAGGACCUCCAGGGCAUGUUGCUCCCUUCUGUCCUCAGCAAGGCUCGGUCCUGGACAUUCUAGGUCCCUGACUCGCCAGAUGCAUCAUGUCCAUUUUGGGAAAAUGGACUGAAGUUUCUGGAGCCCUUGUCUGAGACUGAACCUCCUGAGAAGGGGCCCCUAGCAGCGGUCAGAGGUCCUGUCUGGAUGGAGGCUGGAGGCUCCCCCCUCAACCCCUCUGCUCAGUGCCUGUGGGGAGCAGCCUCUACCCUCAGCAUCCUGGCCACAAGUUCUUCCUUCCAUUGUCCCUUUUCUUUAUCCCUGACCUCUCUGAGAAGUGGGGUGUGGUCUCUCAGCUGUUCUGCCCUCAUACCCUUAAAGGGCCAGCCUGGGCCCAGUGGACACAGGUAAGGCACCAUGACCACCUGGUGUGACCUCUCUGUGCCUUACUGAGGCACCUUUCUAGAGAUUAAAAGGGGCUUGAUGGCUGUUCCAAAGUGUUGAUGGCUGGGAGAAGGGGCCAGAGGAGGAGUGAGGGGUGGGGUUUGUCCAGCCCUGGGCUUUCCGGGCUCUAGAGAUAGCAUGGUGUAGGCUCAAUGACAGUUCUGGGGACAGCAAGUUGGAGGUUCAGGGGCAGCUUCAGGACAGCAGGAUGGAGGCUCAGGGACAAUUCCUGGGAGGCCAGUGCCCUCGUUCCUCCUUGUCCUCAUCCUCCCCCUUGCUCCAGGAAACUGAGAGCUGAGCCUGGAGCUUCCAGACAGUCAGUGCUGGGGGUGACCAUCCAGCAGUGAUGGUGGCCUGUGAAGGGUCCUGCUUCUGUCCUCAGCCUCUCAUGGGGUGGGCUUGUGGAGGAGCUGUGGUCUGGAGAGAGUGGCAGUUGGAGCAGAACGUGCCUGCGUUUGUUUCCUAGGGCUGUCGUAACAAAGUGCCACAAAAUGGUUAGCUUAGAACCACAGAGAUUUGUUGUCUCACAAUUCUGAAGUCCAGAAGUUGGAAAUAAAGAUGUUGGCAGUGUUCCCAACCA